AAAAUCACGUGACCUAUUCACCUGGGCAGAGCGCUUUCCCAAACGCCUGUUCUCUGUGCUUUCUUACUCCUCACUUUCCUCUGUUUUCCGAGGGGGAAACUGACUCAGUAUUGUUCCUUGUCACACGGUUACUACGUUGUAGAGUCUGUUUGAAUCCGCCUGUUUCUUAACUACUGCUAUACUGCCCUCUGCACCAUGGGCUUCUGCUUUGUCUUCUACAUCAUACUUCCCUGUUGUCUAAUCCCCCAAGUGUUUGGACAGAACAAGAUAUUCCUGGUCAGCAUCGUGGUGCACGCCUGUAAUCCCAGCUACUCUGGAGGCUGAGGCAGGAGGAUCGCUUGAGCCCAAGAGUUUGACGUUACAGUCUCAAUGCCAGGAAGCCUCCCGCUCCUAAACAGCGUGUUCGCUUCUUGCUGGGCCCCAUGGAAGGCAGCGAAGAGAAGGAGCUGACCCUCACAGCCACCAGCGUACCCUCUUUCAUCAACCAUCCACUGGUAUGUGGACCAGCAUUCGCCCAUCUCAAGGUUGGCGUGGGACAUCGGUUGGAUGCCCAGGCUUCUGGAGUACUUGUGCUCGGCGUGGGACAUGGAUGCAGGCUCCUCACCGAUAUGUACAAUGCUCAUCUUACCAAGGAUUACACAGUGCGUGGCCUCCUGGGCAAAGCUACAGAUGACUUCCGUGAGGACGGGAGGCUGGUAGAGAAGACAACCUAUGACCACGUGACCAGAGAGAAGCUGGACCGCAUUCUGGCCGUUAUCCAAGGCUCCCAUCAGAAGGCCCUGGUGAUGUACUCCAACCUCGACCUGAAGACCCAGGAGGCCUAUGAGAUGGCCGUGAGAGGCCUGAUCCGGCCCAUGAACAAGUCCCCGAUGCUGAUAACUGGCAUCCGAUGCCUCUACUUUGCACCUCCGGAAUUCCUCUUAGAGGUGCAGUGCAUGCAUGAGACGCAGAAAGAGCUGCGGAAGUUGGUUCAUGAAAUCGGCCUGGAACUAAAGACCACUGCUGUCUGCACCCAAGUGCGGCGCACGCGCGACGGCUUCUUCACGCUAGACAGUGCCCUCCUGAGGACCCAGUGGGACCUAACCAACAUCCAGGAUGCUAUCCGGGCUGCUACCCCUCAGGUAGCUGCAGAGCUGGAGAAGAGCUUGAGCCCGGGGCUGGACACCAAGCAGCUCCCCAGUCCGGGAUGGUCCUGGGACUCCCAGGGCCCGAGCUCUACCUUGGGGCUGGAGAGGGGUGCGGGGCAGUGAAUGCCCAGGCAGCUCCUGGGGCAGUGGAUGGAUAAAUAGAAGAACUGCUAUGAGCUGGACCUGAUAGCUGUGCAGAAAGUGAGAGCAGGGGCACCUUUUCUACGUAAGACACAAAACUCAAGCUGUAACAGAAAGGUCAAUGGACUUGACCCAACUGAGAAGGAAAAACUUCUGUAUGGAGGAAAAGACAGUAAACAUGACAGACUGAUAGAAAGUAUUGGCAGACCAGGCGUGGUGGCGGGCACUUGUAAUCCCAGCUACUCCCAAGGCUGAGGCAGGAGAAUUGCUUGAGCCCAGGAGUUUAAGGUUGUAGUGCGCUAGACGGCGCCUGUGAAUAGCCACUGCACUCUAGUCUGGGGAACAUAUGAGACCCCUGCCAUCUCAAAAAAAAAAAAAUUCUCAAUAAACUAUGUGCCCACGAAAAUUAAAAAUUAAAAAAAAUUGUAAGUAUUUGCAGUGUCAUUAACCAAGGACUAAUAUCCAUAGUAUACAGAGAGCCCUUAGAAAGCAAUAAGAAGACAACGACAAAAUUAGGCAAAUGAGAUGAAGUGUGUAUCAGAAGAAAUCCAAAUGGCUAGUAAGCCAGAAAUGACACUCAACCUCUUUAAUACUGGAAGACACAGAUGAAAAUGAGAUGAUUUUUGUUGUUUUUCUGUUGUUGCCCAGGCUGGAGUGCAGUGGCGCCAUCUUUGCUCACUGCAGCCUCCGCCUCCCAGGUUCAAGUGAUUCUCCUGCCUCAGCCUCCCAAGUAGCUGGGGUCACAGGCGCCCGCCACCACACCUGGCUAAUUUUUUGUAUCCGAGAUGAGGUUUCACCAUGUUGGCCUGGCUCAGCCUCCCAAAGUGCUGGGAUUACAGGCGUGAGCCACCGCACCUGGCCGGGACCUCAGUCUUUUCUCUUAAAGGUCUUCAGUUUAUUGAAUGAGCUCCGCCCACAAUUGUGGUGGAUAAUCAGCGUGACUCAAAGUCUACCCAUUGACUGAUUGAAAUGUUAAUCAUUUUUUUGUUUUUGUUUUUGUUUUUGAGACUUGCUUUGUGGCCCAGGCUGGAGUGCAGUGGUGCGAUCUAGGCUCACUGCAACCUCCGCUUCCCAGGUUCACGCCAUUCUCCUGCCUCAGCCUCCCGAGUAGCUGGGACUACAGGUGCCCACCACCACGCCCAGCUAAUUUUUUUGUAUUUUUAGUAGAGACGGUGUUGCACCGUGUUAGCCAGGAUGGUCUCAAUCUCCUGACCUCGUGAUCCGCCUGGCUUGGCCUCCCAAAGUACUGGGAUUACAGCCGUGAGCCACCACACCCGGCCUGUUUUGGUUUUUUUUUUUUCUGAGACGGAGUCUCACUCCGUCAUCCAGGUUGGAGUGCAGUGGCACAAUCUCAGCUCACUGCAACCUCUGCCUCCCAGGUUCAAGCGAUUCUCCUGCCUCAGCUUCUCAAGUAGCUGGGAUUACAGAUGUGUACCACCAUGCCUGGCUAAUUUUUGUAUUUUUAGUAGAGACAGGGUUUCACCAUGUUGGCCAGGCUGGUCUGGAACUCCUGACCUCAGGUGAUCCGCCCACCUCAGCCUCCCAGAGCGCUGGGAUUAUGCCAACCUCUGCCUCCCAAAGCACUGGGAUGGCAGGCAUGAGCCACCACACCCGGCCUGUUUUUGUUUUUUAGACAGGGUCUUGCUCUGUCACCCAGGCUGGAGUGCAGUGAUGCAAACAUGACUCACUGCAGCUUUGUCCUCUCAGGCUUAACCAUCUUCCCACCUCAGCUUCCAGAAUAGCUGGGACUGCAGGCGUGCACACAGUAUCUGGCUAAUUUAUUUAUUUUAUUUUAUUUUUGAGACAGGGCCUCGCACUGUCGCCCAGGCUAGAGUGCAGUGGCGCGGUUUCAACUCAUUGCAGCCUCGACCCUCCUGGGUCAAGCGAUUCUUCCUGCCUUAGUCUCCAGAGUUGCUGGGAUUACCGGUGUGCACCACCAAGCCUGGCUAAUUUUUGUAUUUUUAGUAGAGACAGGGUUUCACUAUGUUGGCCAGGCUGGUCUGGAACUCCUGACCUGAGGUGAUCCGCCUACCUCGGCCUUCCAAAGUACUGGGAAUAUAGGCAUGAGCCACUGUUUCCGGCCUGUUUUUUUUAGACAGAGUCUUGCUCUGUCACCCAGGCUGGAGUGCAAUGGUGCAAACAUGACUCACUGCACCGUCAUCCUCCCAGGCUCAACCAUCUUCCCACCUCACCCUCCAGAAUAGCUGGGACUACAGGCGUGCACCACGAUGCCUGGCUAAAUAUUUUUUUCCAGCUAAUUUUAUUAUUUUUUUUUGAGAUGGAGUCUUGCUCUGUCACCCAGGCUGGAGUGCAAUGGCACAAUCUUGGCUCACUGCAACCUCCGCCUCCCAGGGUCAAGUGAUUCUCCUGCCUCAGCCACCCAAGUAGCUGGGAUUAUAGGCGUUCACCACCACGCCCAGCUAACUUUUGUAUUUUUAGUAGAGACGGGGUUUCACCAUGUUGGACAUGCUGGUCUCAAAGUCCUGACCUCAGGUGAUCUGCCCGCUUCAGCCUCCCAAAGUGCUGGGAUUACAGGCGUGAGCCACCAUACCUGGCCCACCUGAGAUCAGGAGUUCAAGACCAGCCUGGCCAACAUAGUGAAACCCUGUCUCUACUAAAAAUACAAAAAUUAGCCAGCUAUGGUGACGCACUUCUGUAAUCCUAGCUACUUGGGAGGCUGAGGCACAAGAAUCGCUGAAGCCCAGGAGGUGGAGAUUGCCAUUAGCUGAGAUUGUGCCCCUGCACUCCAGUCUGGACGAGAGAGUGAGACUCUGUCUCAGAAAAGAAAAAAAAAAAGGCUGGGCACGGUGGCUCACGCCUGUAAUCCCAGCACUUUGGGAGGCCAGGGUGGGCGGAUCACGAGGUCAGGAGUUCAAGACCAGCCUGACCAACAUGGUGAAACCUGUCUCUACUAAAAAUACAAAAUUAGCCGGGCGUGCUUGCACGUGCCUGUAGUCCUGGCUACCCGGGAGGCUGAUGCAGAAUAACUGGAACUCGGGAGGCGGAGCUUGCAGUGAGUGGAGAUUGCGCCACUGCACUCCAGCCUAGGUGACAGAGUGAGACUCUGUCUCAAAAAAAAAAAAAAAAGAGAAAAAUCAGAACAAAAUCAGCAAUAUUUAGACAAGCAGAAUCCAAUGAAAUGGUGAGGAAAGCUGGGUGGGAGUGGAGGGUAUCAGCAAAACUCAGUUCUUUGGAAAAAUUAGGUAACUUGAACGUAGGGCACAUGGGCUGUCACACCACCCCAUUUAGAGCCCUUAUUGGCAUAGAGAUGAUAAAAGUGGACUCUGUGAUGGCCUCUCAUGAUCUCAGGAUAGCAGGAUAGGGGAACUCUGAGUCAUGGCCAAAAUAAUUGGUCAAUGUACAGCCUCAGACAGCUGGGAAUACCACCCCAAAUCACUUGGAUAAGGAGAUGUUUUCCUUAUCCUGUGUCUUUAACUCUGAGACGGAUGGAGUUGAACAAUCAACGAUUGUUAAAAAUGUACCAAAUGUGUAAGCAUCAUGAGGUGUUUAAGCUGAGCUUUUAAAUUAAAAUUCUGCUGGGUGUGGCGGCUCAUGCCUGUAAUCCCAGCACUUUGCGAUCCCCACACAGGAGGAUUGCUUGAGCCCAGAAGUUUGAGACCAGCCUGGGCAACACAAGGAGACCCUGUCUCUACAAAAAACAAACAAACAAACAAAAAAGCCGGGGGUGUUGGUGUGUGCCUGUAGUCCCAGCUACUAGGGAGGCUGAGAUGGGAGGAUCGCUUGAACCUAGCAAGUCAAGGCGGCAGUAAAUGGAGAUCUGUACUCCAGCCUGGGCAACAGAGCGAGACCCUAUGUCAGAAAAAAAGAAAAAGCCACCCAGCAGGCUGAGCGUGGUGGCUCACGCCUGUAAUCCCUGCACUUUGGGAAGCCAAAGCAGGUGAAUCACUUGAGGUCAGGAGUUCGAGACCAGCCUGGCCAAUAUGGUGAAACCCUGUCUCUACCAAAAAUACAAAAAUUAGCCGGGCAUGGUGGCGCUUGUCUGUAGUCCAGCUACAGCUACUCCAGAUCUGGGCUGAGGUGGGAGAAUCAUUUGAACCCAGGAGGUGGAGGUUGCAGUGAGCUGAAAUCACACGACUGUACUCUAGCCUGGGUGACAGGGUGAGACCCUAUCUCAAAACAAACAAACAAAAACCCCACCAGCAACCUUGCUGACAAAUCCACAGGCCCCCACGUCUGCCAAUUGCCUGCCUGUAUGAACUGGGCACCUGGGGGAGGGGCGUGGCCCCCAGGCUACUCAUCUUGGCUUUCACAGCCAAAGGGCCUGGGUGGAACCUCAGCUUACUGUGUUUACUGACUGGGUAAUGUGGCCUCUGAAGCUGUCACCUAUCUAUAAAAUGGGGAUUAAAACGACA